GAUUCGGCCAGUGGUGCUGAGCGAGUGCUGGACCAGCGGCCGUCCUGUGCACCUGGCCUGUGCGCGUGCCCGCUGCUCGGCUUCACCCAGACUAAGGCGCGGGCAGCUGCGGGAACAGGCGGGGUGGGCGGAGGGAGACCGGGAGGCACGGGCGCCCUGUGCGCGGAGGAGGUGAAGGCGGCCGGGGCCGGGACGCCAUGUCCAUGGAGGACCCCUUCUUUGUGGUGAAAGGAGAGGUACAGAAAGCAGUCAACACUGCCCAGGGAUUGUUUCAGAGAUGGACAGAGCUCCUCCAGGACCCCUCCACAGCAACAAGGGAAGAAAUCGACUGGACCACCAACGAGCUGAGAAAUAACCUCCGGAGCAUAGAGUGGGAUCUAGAGGACCUUGAUGAAACCAUCAGCAUAGUUGAAGCAAAUCCUAGAAAAUUUAACCUUGAUGCAACUGAAUUGAGUAUAAGAAAAGCCUUCAUUACAAGUACUCGGCAAGUUGUCAGGGACAUGAAAGAUCAGAUGUCAACUUCAUCUGUGCAGGCAUUAGCUGAAAGAAAAAAUAGACAGGCACUGCUGGGAGACAGUGGCAGCCAGAACUGGAGCACUGGAACAACAGAUAAAUAUGGGCGUCUGGACCGAGAGCUCCAGAGAGCCAAUUCUCAUUUCAUUGAGGAGCAGCAGGCACAGCAGCAGUUGAUCGUGGAACAGCAGGAUGAGCAGUUGGAGCUGGUCUCUGGCAGCAUCGGGGUGCUGAAGAACAUGUCCCAGCGCAUCGGAGGGGAGCUGGAGGAACAGGCAGUUAUGUUGGAAGAUUUCUCUCACGAAUUGGAGAGCACUCAGUCCCGGCUGGACAAUGUGAUGAAGAAACUUGCAAAAGUAUCUCAUAUGACCAGUGAUCGGCGCCAAUGGUGUGCCAUAGCCAUCCUCUUUGCAGUCCUGUUGGUUGUGCUCAUCCUCUUCUUAGUGCUGUGACGGCGGGGCCUCUGGGUGCGAGUUCCUCCUGCAUAUGAACCGAGGGGAGGAGGAGAAGCUGAGCACGUGUGACAUUGCCGUCUACUCACAUUCCUAUCCUGGAAACAUACUGCUGCACUGACUUUUCUCCGUGUGACCCCACAAUUGACAUGGCUCCUCCAUCCCAGCGCUGGAAGGGCCAGUGGGAAGAGGAAAUAGAUGUCUGCACUCCUGGCUGCAGCUGGACAACAGAAGCCCCAUGCCGCCUGUCCAGUUCGGAGGAGAACUAGCUGCUGCCUUGCCUUCCGGGACCUCGUUUGCUGAGGAGGGACUUACAGACUCCACUGGUGUUUUGCUGUUGCUCAUUCCAUGCAUCUUUGGCAGCUCUUUUCUUCUGCUCAGACCCUUCCCCGUGCUCAGACAGUGCACCGCUGUCCCAUCUAAAGAAACCUGUCAGGAAUACGAGCUUCUGGGUAUGUUUCGUUUCCCAUUGCUGUAGCAUUUCUUAUCCCCUGAGAGCUGAUGAUUAUUGAGGACAGAAGGCUCAGAAACAGUUUGUGACAGAAAAUGCAGUGUUUCAUUUUUCAGGGAUAAAUGCUAAGAUAAAAUUGCUUUUCCAGGUCAUUUUUUUUUGUGGUAAGAAUAACUAAUGGAAAAUAAUGAAACACCCUGGGGUUUGGGGGUGCUAACAACUUGUGGCUUUAACUGACAGGAGCAAUUAAAAAGAGCAAGAGGGUUCUGCAUUGGCAUAGCUUAGGGAAGGGUUAAUGAUGUCGCCACAGGUCAGCUCCUGAUCCUUGCCGACUUGAUGUUGCUGUACCAGGGCUUCCUCCCCAGAGGUGCAGCUUGCGUUUUGAGGGUGAUUGCUACAUAUGUUGUUGCUAAACAGCUCAGUAACACACUUGAAUGAAUUUGGAUACCAGAUUGUCCUCAUUACAGUUCUUUUACUCUUAGGGCACUCUACACUGGGGGUUGGGGUUGGGAGUGGUUAGUACAUUUAUUACAUUUAUUAAGAAACGUAAUGACAUAAAAGGUUAGCUCUGGGCCAGACUUCUCUUACUCUGUGGGUAAUGGCAAGGAUGUGUAGGUAAACUUGGUUCUUUUUUUUCCCUAAGAUGACAGCUUGAUUUUAUCAUCUGCAGUCAAAUAACUGAGCCAAUCCAAAUUUAAAUGAUAGAUGCUUUAAUUGAGUUUAAGUAGCUGAAACUGCUGAGACACUAAACUUUAACCUUCUGAUGACUUUUUAAAAUGCCUCAAAUGUGCACAUGUAUAUAGGAUAUUUUUAUAACUUCCCUGAUGAAUAAUCUGAUAUUAAAGUAGUAUUUGGACCCAGAGCCAGAACUCGGUGGUGGAGGCUGCUGGUCUCUCCUCACCACCUUCUUUUGCACUUGGAAAGAACAGCAACAUCUGGAUAGAGUUCUAGCUUUGACUUCUCAUUUCCUUGUCUUUUUGGGUGCAUUCCUCAGCACACUUUUUUUUUAAACCUUUUUGUUUUGUUUUGUUUGUAUUUCAUGUGGUUUUAUUUGGGGGUUUUGGUUUUUUCACCCUUUUUUGUGAUUUGCAAUGAUGUGCUUGCCCAGCUAACUUUUGAAUUGCACUUUUUAAUAAAUAUUCUUAACAAUUUUUGAAGAAGGAUAUUUUAUCUCAUUUGAGAUCAUGGUAGGUUAAGAAAAUAUGCCUGUUGAUGAAAGCUAAAAGCAAAUUUAUGAAACUAAAAGGGUGAUUGACAUCCAUGUUUACACUCCGCUCUAAUGUUUGAUAUAUAAAUAAGUUAUUUUCAAAUUAGGAAAAAACAGUGAGUAUUACAAAGGGCUUCAGAUGUUUAGAGUACUAGGUUAUUUAUGUUUUACAAAGUUUGAAUCUUCUAUAAACUAAGAAAGGGGAUGAUCCUUAGAUUUGCAUUAAAAUAUAGAAGUCUUUUAAAGUAAAUGUGAACCUUGUCUAAGUACUGUAAUCCACACAACACAUUAUAAGAAGCAAACCAGCAUCUUAAGGAAUUAUAAAAUUACCCUAUUUAAAAGCCAUGCUAUUGUUCUGCUAUUACCAGAUUUAUUGUGCCACACAAAAGGAUCAUGUGUGUCAGCAGGGGCCGUUUGGAACAAACCUAGUCAUUAAUGAGUAAGAUACUCCUGUUAGUUCAGGGACCAAGUUUUAUGACCCAGAGGCUUAAUGAUGUUUGGAUAUAUUUCAAAUCGGCGUGCUUACCUCACUGAUUUAAAUUAUUUUCUAAAUAGUGGCCAUUGUAGACCUGACUCAGGCUGAAGCUAAAUAGAGAACAAUUUAGAAAGUUAACUAACAAUACAGUGCAUUCUACCCGUAGGGCCACCAUGCCCUUCUGCCCCUGGCUGAUUUGAUCCUGUGUCUGAUCCCAUUGCACCCUGACUGGGCAGUCCCUACAGAACCAGUGUUAAUUUGAAGGGCCUCCACUCAGGCUCCAAAUGUGGCAGCCAAAGAGAACAAUCCAGGGAACCUACAUUUAUUUUUAAGGACAAAUAUUUCCUCCUCAGUGGUCCUAAUGUUCAGGGCUUUAGAGGGAACCCAGGUGGUCUCUUCACCCUGUGUCCUAGAAUGGGAGAGUAAGUAGACAGUGGUGAUAACCCCACACUGCUUAUAAGUGCAUCUUUAUAGUAUUUGGGGCUUUCCUACCCCUUUAGCCUUCUGUACCUAGUACCAUAUUCCAGUUUUAAAGAACUGGCAGAAUGUGAUGGAUAACAGAGGAAGAGCUCAAUUUAUGUUUAUUGGAAGAACAUUUUACUUAAAUGAUUUGAGGGGUGGGAGGGAGUGAACUACUGAGUUUGCCAGAGUGAAAAUCCAUCUGAAAAACUCAGCUACCUUUAGUUUUUAGUCCUCAUUUUUGGUCUUGUCUCUGCGGACUGUGAAGAAUCACAAUGCUCUAUAUGCCCUGGACUGUGUGGCAAAUGCAGGUUGCAGCGUGUGUGUUACAUGAGGAUCUUCCACAAUUUCAGAAUGCACGCCAGAGCUGAAGGGGGAAACUUGGUAACUUGCCCAUUAUUCUCUGCUUUUAGCCAGAGUUAAACAGACUGAUGGGUCUGGUAGCCAACAACUUGGCAACUUCCACUCCUUCUCACCUCGUGAGAUUAAGGGCUGUGAAAAGAAAUCUAGUCUAACUCCAACAGAAAUCUGUCUCUGUUAAGUGUUUUACCUUCUGUAAGUAGAGAUGGUAGAGCCAAGAUUUUUCUUUUGGUAAUUUCCCUGUCUAUAAAGUGAGACCAAAGGGAUAUCUGUUCCCUGUUACCUUUUUGGAGAAUUCAUAACAUUUGAAGAUCAAAAAAUUGAAUGAUAAAUAUGAAUGGCUUUUCAAUUCUGUGGACUUUGUACCAUUUGGCUUCACCUUGUACUGCAAGAUGAAUUUGUAAACAAAACAAAAUUGGACUGUCUGGAAAGCUAAAGUUCUGAAAUAUGGAAUGUACUGCCUCUAAUUUUUCUUUGUCUUCCUCUCACUGGCAUUUUUUUCUCUCCCAGGUUUCUUAAGAAUAAUGUUUUUUAAAGGAGGCUUUUUGCCCAUCAAGAAUAAAAAGAAAUAAAACCAAAGGGUUACCGGACUUAAGCCCCCGCAGUCACUGUGCGCCAUCCCUGAGCAAAGUCCGCCCCUGAGGACAGUGCCCCUGCCCCAGUGACAGGCCUUACUCCUCCCAGGGCCUUUGCUUCUAAUAGGGGGUGGUCUUUCUUUUCUUUCUCUCCUUUUUUUUUUUUUGAUUAAAAAAUAAAACCAAACCAGAAUUUGCUGAAAGCAGGUACCUUUCAGUAGCUCCGAUCAGAGUAACUCAGCUUAGAGAUACUGUUACUCAGGACAACAGUAUGUACAAAAGUCUCCGGAAAAGGAAAAUAAAACAACCUGAAAAGAA